GAGACUGGCGUCCGGUGUGCAGGUGGCCACAUGGAUCCUGGCAGCCGGUGGCGGAACCUGCCCAGCGGGCCUAGCCUAAAGCACUUGACUGACCCCUCUUAUGGAAUCCCGCGGGAACAGCAAAAGGCAGCGUUGCAGGAGCUGACGCGGGCGCACGUGGAGUCCUUCAACUACGCUGUGCACGAGGGUCUCGGCCUCGCGGUGCAGGAUCUCACUUUGUCACCUAGGCUGGAAUGCAGUGGCAUGGUUAUAGCUCACUGCAGCCUCGACCUUCCAGGAUCAAGUGAUCCUCCCACGUCAACCUCUUGAGUAGCUGGGACCACAGGCGUGCACCACUAUGCCCGGCUAAUUUUUUUAUUUUUAUUUUUUGUAGAGACGGGGUCUCCCUAUGUGGCCCAGCCUGGUCUCAAACUCCUGAGCUCAAGUAGUCCUCCUCUCUCGGUCUCCCAAAUAUUGGGAUUACAGGCUAUACCUCCCUUUGAAUUUGCUUUCAAAGAUGAGCGUAUCUCUUUUACUAUUCUGGAUGCUGUUAUCAGUCCACCUACAGUUCCAAAAGGGACCAUCUGCAAAGAGGCCAAUGUUUAUCCAGCAGAAUGCCGGGGCCGAAGGAGUACCUACCGUGGGAAGUUGACAGCUGAUAUCAACUGGGCAGUGAAUGGAAUCUCAAAAGGAAUCAUUAAGCAGUUUCUUGGCUAUGUUCCCAUCAUGGUGAAAUCCAAGCUUUGCAACUUACGUAACCUUCCCCCACAAGCCCUCAUUGAGCACCAUGAGGAGGCAGAGGAAAUGGGGGGCUAUUUUAUAAUCAAUGGCAUUGAAAAAGUCAUCCGAAUGUUGAUUAUGCCUCGGAGAAAUUUUCCCAUUGCAAUGAUAAGACCAAAAUGGAAAACCAGAGGGCCUGGUUAUACUCAGUAUGGAGUUUCAAUGCACUGUGUGAGGGAAGAACAUUCCGCUGUCAAUAUGAACCUCCACUACUUGGAAAAUGGCACUGUUAUGUUGAACUUUAUUUACCGAAAAGAACUGUUCUUUCUUCCUUUGGGAUUUGCACUUAAGGCACUUGUCAGCUUUUCUGAUUAUCAGAUCUUUCAGGAGCUCAUCAAAGGAAAAGAGGAUGAUUCUUUCCUUAGGAACUCUGUUUCUCAGAUGUUAAGGAUUGUAAUGGAAGAGGGUUGUUCGACACAAAAACAGGUCCUUAACUACCUAGGUGAAUGCUUCAGAGUAAAACUCAAUGUUCCUGACUGGUACCCAAAUGAGCAAGCUGCGGAGUUCCUGUUUAACCAGUGCAUCUGUAUCCACUUGAAAUCCAAUACUGAAAAGUUUUAUAUGCUUUGUCUCAUGACGCGAAAGCUCUUUGCUUUAGCCAAAGGAGAGUGCAUGGAGGACAAUCCUGAUAGUUUGGUGAACCAGGAAGUCCUCACACCGGGUCAGCUCUUCCUUAUGUUCCUGAAGGAAAAACUGGAAGGUUGGUUAGUGUCUAUUAAAAUAGCUUUUGAUAAGAAGGCUCAGAAGACCAGUGUUUCCAUGAACACUGACAAUUUGAUGAGGAUUUUUACAAUGGGCAUAGACCUUACAAAACCAUUUGAAUACCUUUUUGCUACUGGGAAUCUGCGUUCUAAAACAGGUCUUGGCCUCCUACAAGAUUCUGGACUUUGUGUUGUGGCUGACAAGCUGAACUUCAUACGCUACCUCUCCCAUUUCCGCUGCGUGCACAGAGGGGCUGAUUUUGCCAAGAUGAGGACCACCACAGUACGCAGGCUGCUGCCAGAGUCCUGGGGCUUCCUUUGUCCCGUGCAUACCCCAGACGGGGAGCCCUGUGGCCUGAUGAACCACCUAACUGCCGUAUGUGAGGUUGUCACACAGUUUGUGUAUACGGCAUCUAUUCCAGCUUUACUGUGCAACUUGGGGGUCACUCCCAUUGAUGGAGCUCCCCACCGAUCAUACAGUGAGUGCUACCCUGUCCUGCUGGACGGUGUCAUGGUUGGCUGGGUGGAUAAGGAUCUUGCUCCAGGCAUCGCAGAUUCUCUUCGUCAUUUUAAGGUGUUGAGAGAGAAAAGAAUUCCUCCCUGGAUGGAAGUGGUCCUUAUACCCAUGACAGGAAAACCAAGUCUGUACCCAGGAUUGUUCCUUUUUACCACUCCUUGUAGACUGGUACGGCCUGUGCAGAACUUAGCAUUGGGCAAAGAAGAGCUAAUUGGAACUAUGGAACAGAUCUUCAUGAAUGUCGCUAUCUUUGAGGAUGAAGUUUUUGCUGGAGUUACCACACACCAGGAACUCUUUCCACACAGCCUGCUGAGUGUGAUUGCCAACUUCAUCCCUUUCUCUGAUCACAACCAGAGUCCACGGAACAUGUACCAAUGCCAGAUGGGUAAGCAAACUAUGGGCUUUCCACUUCUCACUUAUCAAGACCGAUCGGAUAACAAACUGUAUCGUCUUCAGACUCCUCAGAGUCCCUUGGUGAGACCCUCCAUGUAUGAUUAUUAUGACAUGGAUAACUAUCCAAUUGGGACCAAUGCCAUCGUUGCUGUGAUUUCUUACACUGGCUAUGAUAUGGAAGAUGCCAUGAUUGUGAAUAAGGCCUCUUGGGAACGAGGCUUUGCCCAUGGAAGUGUCUACAAGUCUGAGUUCAUAGACCUCUCUGAAAAAAUUAAACAAGGAGAUAGUAGCCUGGUGUUUGGCAUCAAACCUGGUGACCCACGCGUUCUGCAGAAGUUAGAUGACGAUGGAUUGCCGUUUAUAGGAGCAAAACUGCAGUACGGAGAUCCGUAUUACAGCUACCUCAACCUCAACACCGGGGAAAGUUUUGUGAUGUACUAUAAGAGUAAAGAAAAUUGUGUUGUGGAUAACAUCAAAGUGUGCAGUAAUGACACUGGGAGUGGAAAAUUCAAGUGUGUUUGCAUCACUAUGAGAGUGCCUCGGAACCCAACUAUCGGAGAUAAAUUUGCCAGUCGCCAUGGGCAGAAGGGCAUUUUAAGCAGAUUGUGGCCGGCUGAGGACAUGCCUUUUACUGAGAGUGGGAUGGUCCCAGACAUUCUGUUCAAUCCCCAUGGUUUUCCAUCCCGCAUGACCAUUGGGAUGUUAAUUGAGAGUAUGGCCGGGAAGUCUGCAGCUUUGCAUGGUCUCUGCCAUGAUGCUACACCCUUCAUCUUCUCAGAGGAGAACUCGGCCUUAGAAUACUUUGGUGAGAUGUUAAAGGCUGCUGGCUACAAUUUCUAUGGCACCGAGAGGUUAUAUAGUGGCAUCAGUGGGCUAGAACUGGAAGCAGACAUCUUCAUAGGAGUGGUUUAUUAUCAGCGCUUACGCCAUAUGGUCUCAGACAAAUUUCAAGUAAGGACAACUGGAGCCCGAGACAGAGUCACCAACCAGCCUAUUGGGGGAAGAAAUGUCCAGGGUGGAAUCCGUUUUGGGGAGAUGGAACGGGAUGCGCUUUUAGCUCAUGGUACAUCUUUUCUCCUUCAUGACCGCCUCUUCAACUGCUCAGAUCGGUCGGUAGCCCAUGUGUGUGUGAAGUGUGGCAGUUUACUCUCUCCACUGUUGGAGAAGCCACCCCCUUCUUGGUCUGCCAUGCGCAACAGAAAAUACAACUGUACUCUGUGUAGUCGCAGUGACACUAUCGAUACUGUUUCUGUGCCUUAUGUUUUUCGGUAUUUUGUAGCUGAACUGGCAGCUAUGAACAUCAAAGUGAAACUGGAUGUUGUUUAACUUGAUGUUGACCUUUUGGAUUAAGAGGACUAUCAGAUUAAAGCAAAAUGUAAUUUUAAUUCAAUGAAGAUAUCAUUACCAGGUUACUCUUGAGAUUUUUCAACGGUGUUAGAACUCUCAACCAAGACCUGAAAACCAAGUAUGCAAGGUUUCUGAAUCUCUCUGGUAGAUUAACUAUUGACAAUGAUUUUCUGUUAUCUUUGUUCAAAAAGUUCAUGUCUUCUCAAAAUAUGAAAUAUUGAUAAAUGGAAGAGCAUACGGUGACAAGUCUCCUUUCCAACCCCAGGUUCCCUACACCCUGCUCUCAGCAGGCAGUGAGUGUCACACACCUGUUAAUCCAUCUUGAGCAGGACAGUACUAUACAAAUAGAAUGCAAGCUGUAAUGUAAUUUUAUAUUUUCUUAUAGCCACGUUGAAGUAAAAACAAACAGGUACAGUGUUUUUUACCAGCUUUAUAGAAGUACAGUUGUUACAUAUUUAAUGAAUACAAUUUGAUGGGUCUGACUAUAUGCACACACCUUUGAUACCAUCACCACAAUCAGGGUAAUAAACAUACCUGUCAUCUCCACAAGUUUCCUCCUGCCCCUUUGUUUUUUGCUUUUUGGUUGCUGUUGAGUUUUUGUUUUGUCUUCUGUGGUAAGAACACUUAACUCAAGACCUACCCUCUUAACAAAUCUUUAAGUGCACGAUAUAGUAUUGUUAAUUCCAGGCACCAUGUUGUACAACAGAUCUUUAGACCUUACUUGUCUUGCAUAACUGAAGCUUUAUACCUGUUGAACAACUCUCCAUUUCCCUGGCCCCUAGCAACCACCCUUCUACCCUGUUUCUAUGAGUUUGACUAUUACAGAUAUCUCAUAUAGUGGGAUCAUGCAAUAUUUGUCCUGUGACUGGCUUAUUUCACUUAGCAUAGUGAAAUAAGAUUCAUCCAUUUUGGAAGCCAGGCAUGGUGCUGUGCAUCUAUAGUCCCUGCUAUUUGAGAGGCUGAGGUGGGAGGAUCAUUUGAGUGCAGGAGUUCAAGGACAGCCUGGGUAAUAUAGGAAGACCCUGUCUUGAAGACCCUGACCUCAAGUGAUCCACCCACCUCGGCCUCCGAAAGUGCUAGGAUUACAGGUGUGAGCCACUGUGCCUGGCCUCCGGUGAGUAUUUUAUAUUUAGUCUACACUUCCAUACUUGGCUUUUUUCUGCUUUUAUAUUGAUCUGCUUUCAUAGCAGUGUGUAGAGUGCCACUUAUGUUUUCUUUCUUGUGUACAGUAUUUUAUUGUAUGGAUUUACCAUCCCCUGUGUAUUUAAGUUGUUCCAUUCUUUGGCCAUUAUAACUUUUUUCUGCAAAUAUUCUGGUGACUUAUCUUUGGCCAUUAUAAACUGUUGAUAAUAGAUCAUCUUGUAUAUACUUCUGCAAUUAUAAGAUGUUUUUUGAUGAUGAAAGCUUUCCUAAGGUAAUUCUUUCCUGAGUUUGGUUCAGAUGGUCUGUCACUAAUUAUAAGGCAGAUAGGAACAGACAGAAAAAUCUAUCAUUUCAAGAUAGGCUUAGCAGGAUGGGCGCAGUGGCUCACGCCACUAAUCCCAACAUUUUAGGAGGCCUAGGCAGGAGCAAUCACUUGUGCCUGGGAGUUCUAGACUAGCCUGGGCGAGACUUCAUCUCUACAAAAAAAGCAACAACGACAAAAAAAAUUAGCCAAGCAUAGUGGCACACCCCUGUAGUCCCAGCUACUUGGGAGGCUGAGGUGGGAGGAUUGCUUGAACCCAAGAGGUCGAGGCUGCAGUGAGCCAAGAUUGUGCCACUGCACUCCAGCCUGGGUGACAGAGCAGGACCCUGUCUCUAUUUUAUAAAUUAAAAAAGGCUGGGUGUGGUGGCUCACACCCAUAAUCCCAACACUUUGGCUCAGCAGAUUGCUUGAACCCAGGAAUUCAAGUCCAAUCUGGGCAACAUGGGGAAACCCCAGCUCUACAAAAAAAAUUAGCCUGGUGUGGUGGCACAUGCCUGUAGUUCCAGCUACUCAGGAGGCUGAGGUGGGAGAAUCUCCUGAGCCUGGAAGGUCCAGGCAGUGAGCCAAGAUUGUGCCACCACACUCCAGCCUGGGCGACAGAAUGAGACCCUGUCUCAAAAAAAAAAAAAAAAAAAAAGCGGGGAGGCAUAAGAAAAAACCAAUUUAAUAGAAAAGAUAGGCUUUGCUUCAGGAAGCUGGUUGAGAAGAAGAAGGAAAAAGUCGAUUCUACUGACUGACGUUUCCCCCUGCUGUUAAGAAUCCCAACCACACACUUUCACACACUAUUCCAGGUUCUGGCUACUGAAUGAUCCCACAGCUGAGGUCUAUUGUCAUCGCUCCACUUCUAUUUUUAGCAGCACUAAAAACAUUCCCAAAAAAAAUGUUUUUUAGCUUUUUAACUGUAGAUUCACCACUAAGAAAUUGGCAUUGGAACAGUCCACAGAGCUUAUUCAAAUUUCACCCAUUUUACAUGCACUCAUUUGUGUUGCAUGUGAUAUAUAGUUCUAUUUCAUUUUAUCACCUGUGUAGAUGGAUGAAAACAGCAACAUAAGCAAGAUACAGAGCUGUUCCGUCAUCACAGAGCUCUGCCAUACUAUCCUUUUAUAGCCAUCUCUACCUCUGUCCCCCAUUUCUAACCCCUGGAAACCACUAAUCUGUUCUUCAUAAUUUUCUUAUUUCAAGAAUCUUACGUAAAUAGGAUCACGAAGUAUAACCUUUGAGAAUGGCCUUUUCACUCCAUUCCCUUGAGAUACAUCCAGGUAGUUGCAUGUAUCAAUAGUUAAUUCCUUUUUAUUGCUACACAGUACUCCAUAGUAUGAAUAUACUAUGUACAUAGCAUAUAUAUUUAUAGUUUAACCAUUCACCUUGAACAUUUUGGUUGUUUCCAGUUUGGGGGCAUUAACAAUAAAGCUGAUCUGAACAAUCAGGUAUAAUAGUCCCCCUUUAUCUUUGAAGAUUAUAUCCCAAGACUCCCAGUGAGUGUCUGAAACCAUGGAUAGUAUAUACACUAUCCAUAUGUGCUAUAUGUACUAUAUGUCCUCUAUAUAUUUUUUCUAUACAUACAUACCUUUGAUGUUUAAUUAAGCACUGCAAGAAACUGACAGCAAUAAAUAGAACAAUUAUACUGUAAUUAAAUGAAUGUGGCCUCAAAAUGUACUGUUCUCACAUAUUUUCAGACUGUGGGUAACUGAAACUGCAUAAAGCAAAACUGGCUGGGUGCGGUGGUGCACACCUGUAAUCCCAGGACUUUGGCAGGCUGAGGUGUGCAGAUCACUUGAGGUCAGGAGUUUGAGACCAGCCUGGCCAUCAUGGGGAAACCCCGUCUCUAUUAAAAAUACAAAAAUUAGCUGGGUGUGAUGGCACACGCCUGUAAUCCCAGCUACUCAGGAGGCUGAGACAGGAGAAUCACUUGAACCCAGGAGGCAGAGGUUGCAGUGAGCCAAGAUCACGCCACUGCACAGCAACCUGGGCAACAGAGCAAGACUAGAGUCUCAAAAAAAAAAAAAAAAAAAAAAAAAAAAAAAAGGAAAGCAAAAUUGUAGAUAAGGAGGACUACUAUACAGGUUAUUGUGUAAACAUAAGUUUCAUUUCCCUGGGACAAGUGUUCAAGACUGGGAUUGCUGGGUCAUAUGGUAGUUGCAUAUUUCAUUUAAUAAACUGCCAAACUUUUCAGAGUGGCUGUGCCAUUUUACAUUCCUACCAGCAAUGUAUAAGUGAUUCAUUUCUUGGCAUUCUGACCAACCAGCAUUUGGUGAUGUCACUUUUUUUUUAAGGCUAGUCAAGUGAAGCAGUGGGAGUGGAAAAAGAACAAAUAAAUCUGUAAGUGGUUGUGAUCAAUUUGUUGCAACACCAUUGCACUUGGACCAGCCCACUAUUUCUUAUUUUAGCCAUUCUGAUAGAUGUGUAGUGAUAUCUCAUUGUGGCUUUAAUUUGCAUUUCUCUAAUGGCUGAAAAUGUUGAACAUCUCUUCAUGUGUUUAUUUGCCAUCUGUGUAUCUUCAGUGAAAUGUCUGCUGUUCAUUUUUUAAUUGGAUUGUUUGUCUUCUUACUGUUGAAUUUCAAGACUUCAUUAUAUAUUCCAGAUAUAAAGCCUUUGUCAUACAA